GAGUGGUGUUCAGGAGCUUGAAGGUGCAAACAGCAGCUGCCUUGGGGGCUUACAGCAUAGCAAGCAGAACCUCUCCCAUGCCCUCGGGGCUGGCGUGGGGUGUGGCGGCCCCUCCUGCUGCUCAAGGCUCACCAUACCUGGCUGGCGGCAGGGUCAUUGCCAGCGUCCACCCUCAGGGCCUUUGCGCCUGCCAGGAGCACAGUGUGCGUGACAGCCUCCUGGAGCACGAGCCUCCUGGAACGACAGCCUCCUGCAGCACCUCCCCUCCUUCACGGCGCCGUUUCCUUCUCCCUCAGCCUGUUUCGUAAACAUGUUCUGGGUCCCUGCAGUGUGUCCCUGCAGAGUCCCCUCAGAGACUCUGUCCUAGCCACAUCUGGGUCUCUCGCUCACCAGCCCAUCUCCAGGCCCCCGUGUCUGGCGCCUGUUGGCUCUUUGCUAAAUUUCAUGGCCUCCCACGGGAACGACGCCGCGAGAGCCAGGUUUGAGUCCAAAGUACCCUCCUUCUACUACCGGCCCACGCCCUCCGACUGCCAGCUCCUUCGAGAGCAGUGGAUCCGGGCCAAGUACGAGCGACAGGAGUUCAUCUACCCGGAGAAGCAGGAGCCCUACUCGGCAGGGUACCGUGAGGGUUUUCUCUGGAAGCGUGGCCGGGACAACGGGCAGUUUUUGAGCCGGAAGUUUGUGCUGACAGAACGAGAGGGUGCUCUGAAGUAUUUCAACAGAAAUGAUGCCAAGGAGCCCAAGGCCGUGAUGAAGAUCGAGCACCUGAACGCCACCUUCCAGCCGGCCAAGAUCGGCCACCCCCACGGCCUGCAGGUCACCUACCUGAAGGACAACAGCACCCGUAACAUCUUCAUCUACCAUGAGGACGGGAAGGAGAUUGUGGACUGGUUCAAUGCACUCCGAGCUGCUCGCUUCCACUACCUGCAGGUGGCAUUCCCAGGGGCCGGCGACGCAGAUCUGGUGCCAAAGCUCUCCAGGAACUACCUGAAGGAAGGCUACAUGGAGAAGACGGGGCCCAAGCAAACGGAAGGCUUCCGGAAGCGCUGGUUCACCAUGGAUGACCGCAGGCUCAUGUACUUCAAAGACCCCCUGGACGCCUUCGCCCGAGGGGAAGUCUUCAUUGGCAGCAAGGAGAGUGGCUACACGGUGCUGCAUGGGUUCCCGCCGUCCACCCAGGGCCACCACUGGCCACAUGGCAUCACCAUCGUCACGCCCGACCGCAAGUUUCUGUUUGCCUGCGAGACGGAGUCCGACCAGAGGGAGUGGGUGGCGGCCUUCCAGAAGGCGGUGGACAGGCCCAUGCUGCCCCAGGAGUACGCAGUGGAGGCGCACUUCAAGCAUAAACCUUAGCGAGUGCGGCUGGAGGACCACGGACAUUGGACUCACUGUGGCUGGACGGAGGGGACCCGUGGAUGGGGGGGCUCUGGCGUCCUGAGGCCACCUGGCCCCACCUGCUCCUCAGGGCAGCCCGGCGCGGCCAGGUAGGGCCCGAGCUUCAGCUUCCAGGAUGCUUCUCUGGAACCUCAAGGCAGGCAGCCCAGGCCCUGGGCCUGAUCUCUAACCCCGUCAUGCUGCUGCUGACCACACCCAGCCAACCUGCCCCUCCCUGACCCGGGGCCCCCUUUCCUCCAGGGCCCAGUCUGGCUCCCGAGCUCAGACACAGCCCCCAGGAGCCGCCCACCACGGCUGUGGGAACUUCCAGGCCUCAGCGCAGAGCCCUGCUUGGGGCCAGCACGGUGGGCAGCUGCCGGCCGCUGGGGACUGGGCCCUGCUCGCAUGCCGCCCCGCCCUCCCCCCACCUCCACGACUAUUUAUUGAGCGCCUGUUGUGUGUCACGGGGCUAUGAGGGCCGUGGGGUGUUUGGGUGGAUUAUCCACACAGGUCCCGGCCCCUGCCCGGGCUGGAGUUGCCACAGCCUGUGCUCCUGGUCCUCACCUGGAGGGGCCAGCAGGCUGCCGUCCCACCACACGUGGCCUCUGCGCCCAGCACGGUGCUCGCCGACAGUGGUGUCUGAACCCUUGGGGACGAGGGCCUGGGCCGCGGUGAGGCCACCAGAGGCAGGAGUGGCCCUGGGGGUCCCGGGCACUGUCGCGCUUGCUGCAGGCGGCCCAGCCGUGUAUUUAUUUUUCACCUAUCUCCUUCCUGUCAAGGCAGGCCGGGCUCCAGGGCUCCCCUUGCGUGGGGCAUGUAGGUGGGGGAGGCGUCUGCAGGUCACCUGGGGGGCCCAGCCCUCUCCCAGCCUUGCCUGGCUGAGCUGUGUUCCAGGGGAGCCCUGGACAAGCCCUCAUAGGCAGGGAGGGGGUUUCCGAGGCCAGGCAUCCGCCGCCCCGUGUCGCAUCCUGGAAUAAAAUGUGGCUCUGGCAUGGUUCCA